GCACUUCUAAGAACUAACCUUUAGUCACUGGGUGACUUUAUGGGAGUAAAAGGAAGCUGUUAUGAAAUAGCUCUUAUGGAACUGUUACAAGCUUUCAAGCAUUCAAAGGUCUAAAUGAAAAAGGCUAAGUAUUAUUUCAAAAGGCAAGUAUAUCCUAAUAUAGCAAAACAAACAAAGCAAAAUCCAUCAGCUACUCCUCCAAUUGAAGUGAUGAAGCCCAAAUAAUUCAUAUAGCAAAAUGGAGAAAAUUAGACCGGCCAUCUAAAAAUCUGCCAUUGGUGAAGUGAUGAAGAACAUUUACUGUCUUAUUCCGAAGCUUGUCAAUUUUGCAACUCUUGGCUGCCUAUGGAUUUCUGUGGUGCAGUGUACAGUUUUAAAUAGCUGCCUAAAGUCGUGUGUAACUAAUCUGGGCCAGCAGCUUGACCUUGGCACACCACAUAAUCUGAGUGAACCGUGUAUCCAAGGAUGUCACUUUUGGAACUCUGUAGAUCAGAAAAACUGUGCUUUAAAGUGUAAUGAUACUUAUGCCACCGUUUGUGAGCGGGAGUCGUGUGAGGUUGGCUGUAGCAGCGCGGAAGGUGCAUAUGAAGAGGAAGUACUGGAAAAUGCAGACCUACCAACUGCUCCCUUUGCUUCUUCCAUUGGAAGCCACAAUAUGACAUUACGAUGGAAAUCUGCAAACUUCUCUGGAGUAAAAUACAUCAUUCAGUGGAAAUAUGCACAACUUCUGGGAAGCUGGACUUAUACUAAGACUGUGUCCAGACCGUCCUAUGUGGUCAAGCCCCUGCACCCCUUCACUGAGUACAUUUUCCGAGUGGUUUGGAUCUUCACAGCGCAGCUGCAGCUCUACUCCCCUCCAAGUCCCAGUUACAGGACUCAUCCUCAUGGAGUUCCUGAAACUGCACCUUUGAUUAGGAAUAUUGAGAGCUCAAGUCCCGACACUGUGGAAGUCAGCUGGGAUCCACCUCAAUUCCCAGGUGGACCUAUUUUGGGUUAUAACUUAAGGCUGAUCAGCAAAAAUCAAAAAUUAGAUGCAGGGACACAGAGAACCAGUUUCCAGUUUUACUCCACUUUACCAAAUACUAUCUACAGGUUUUCUAUUGCAGCAGUAAAUGAAGUUGGUGAGGGUCCAGAAGCAGAAUCUAGUAUUACCACUUCAUCUUCAGCAGUUCAACAAGAGGAACAGUGGCUCUUUUUAUCCAGAAAAACUUCUCUAAGAAAGAGAUCUUUAAAACAUUUAGUAGAUGAAGCACAUUGCCUUCGGUUGGAUGCUAUAUACCAUAAUAUUACAGGAAUAUCUGUUGAUGUCCACCAGCAAAUUGUUUAUUUCUCUGAAGGAACUCUCAUAUGGGCGAAGAAGGCUGCCAACAUGUCUGAUGUAUCUGACCUGAGAAUUUUUUACAGAGGUUCAGGAUUAAUUUCUUCUAUCUCCAUAGAUUGGCUUUAUCAAAGAAUGUAUUUCAUCAUGGAUGAACUGGUAUGUGUCUGUGAUUUAGAGAACUGCUCAAACAUCGAGGAAAUUACUCCACCCUCUAUUAGUGCACCUCAAAAAAUUGUGGCUGAUUCAUACAAUGGGUAUGUCUUUUACCUCCUGAGAGAUGGCAUUUAUAGAGCAGACCUUCCUGUACCAUCUGGCCGGUGUGCAGAAGCUGUGCGUAUUGUGGAGAGUUGCACGUUAAAGGACUUUGCAAUCAAGCCACAAGCCAAGCGAAUCAUUUACUUCAAUGACACUGCCCAAGUCUUCAUGUCAACAUUUCUGGAUGGCUCUGCUUCCCAUCUCAUCCUACCUCGCAUCCCCUUUGCUGAUGUGAAAAGUUUUGCUUGUGAAAACAAUGACUUUCUUGUCACAGAUGGCAAGGUCAUUUUCCAACAGGAUGCUUUGUCUUUUAAUGAAUUCAUCGUGGGAUGUGACCUGAGUCACAUAGAAGAAUUUGGGUUUGGUAACUUGGUCAUCUUUGGCUCAUCCUCCCAGCUGCACCCUCUGCCAGGCCGCCCGCAGGAGCUUUCGGUGCUGUUUGGCUCUCACCAGGCUCUUGUUCAAUGGAAGCCUCCUGCCCUUGCCAUAGGAGCCAAUGUCAUCCUGAUCAGUGAUAUUAUUGAACUCUUUGAAUUAGGCCCUUCUGCCUGGCAGAACUGGACCUAUGAGGUGAAAGUAUCCACCCAAGACCCUCCUGAAGUCACUCAUAUUUUCUUGAACAUAAGUGGAACCAUGCUGAAUGUACCUGAGCUGCAGAGUGCUAUGAAAUACAAGGUUUCUGUGAGAGCAAGUUCUCCAAAGAGGCCAGGCCCCUGGUCAGAGCCCUCAGUGGGUACUACCCUGGUGCCAGCUAGUGAACCACCAUUUAUCAUGGCUGUGAAAGAAGAUGGGCUUUGGAGUAAACCAUUAAAUAGCUUUGGCCCAGGAGAGUUCUUAUCCUCUGAUAUAGGAAAUGUGUCAGACAUGGAUUGGUAUAACAACAGCCUCUACUACAGUGACACGAAAGGCGACGUUUUUGUGUGGCUGCUGAAUGGGACGGAUAUCUCAGAGAAUUAUCACCUACCCAGCAUUGCAGGAGCAGGGGCUUUAGCUUUUGAGUGGCUGGGUCACUUUCUCUACUGGGCUGGAAAGACAUAUGUGAUACAAAGGCAGUCUGUGUUGACGGGACACACAGACAUUGUUACCCACGUGAAGCUAUUGGUGAAUGACAUGGUGGUGGAUUCAGUUGGUGGAUAUCUCUACUGGACCACACUCUAUUCAGUGGAAAGCACCAGACUAAAUGGGGAAAGUUCCCUUGUACUACAGACACAGCCUUGGUUUUCUGGGAAAAAGGUAAUUGCUCUAACUUUAGACCUCAGUGAUGGGCUCCUGUAUUGGUUGGUUCAAGACAGUCAAUGUAUUCACCUGUACACAGCUGUUCUUCGGGGACAGAGCAGCACUGGGGAUACCACCAUCACAGAAUUUGCAGCCUGGAGUACUUCUGAAAUUUCCCAGAAUGCACUGAUGUACUAUAGUGGUCGGCUGUUCUGGAUCAAUGGCUUUAGGAUUAUCACAACUCAAGAAAUAGGUCAGAAAACCAGUGUCUCUGUUUUGGAACCAGCCAGAUUUAAUCAGUUCACAAUUAUUCAGACAUCCCUUAAGCCCCUGCCAGGGAACUUUUCCUUUACCCCUAAGGUUAUUCCAGAUUCUGUUCAAGAGUCUUCAUUUAGGAUUGAAGGAAAUGCUUCAAGUUUUCAAAUCCUGUGGAAUGGUCCCCCUGCGGUAGACUGGGGUGUAGUUUUCUACAGUGUAGAAUUUAGUGCUCAUUCUAAGUUCUUGGCUAGUGAACAACACUCUUUACCUGUAUUUACUGUGGAAGGACUGGAACCUUAUGCCUUAUUUAAUCUUUCUGUCACUCCUUAUACCUACUGGGGAAAGGGCCCCAAAACAUCUCUGUCACUUCGAGCACCUGAAACAGUUCCAUCAGCACCAGAGAACCCCAGAAUAUUUAUAUUACCAAGUGGAAAAUGCUGCAACAAGAAUGAAGUUGUGGUGGAAUUUAGGUGGAACAAACCUAAGCAUGAAAAUGGGGUGUUAACAAAAUUUGAAAUUUUCUACAAUAUAUCCAAUCAAAGUAUUACAAACAAAACAUGUGAAGACUGGAUUGCUGUCAAUGUCACUCCCUCAGUGAUGUCUUUUCAACUUGAAGGCAUGAGUCCCAGAUGCUUUAUUGCCUUCCAGGUUAGGGCCUUUACAUCUAAGGGGCCAGGACCAUAUGCUGACGUUGUAAAGUCUACAACAUCAGAAAUCAACCCAUUUCCUCACCUCAUAACUCUUCUUGGUAACAAGAUAGUUUUUUUAGAUAUGGAUCAAAAUCAAGUUGUGUGGACGUUUUCAGCAGAAAGAGUUAUCAGUGCCGUUUGCUACACAGCUGAUAAUGAGAUGGGAUAUUAUGCUGAAGGGGACUCACUCUUUCUUCUGCACUUGCACAAUCGCUCUAGCUCUGAGCUUUUCCAAGAUUCACUGGUUUUUGAUAUCACAGUUAUUACAAUUGACUGGAUUUCAAGGCACCUCUACUUUGCACUGAAAGAAUCACAAAAUGGAAUGCAAGUAUUUGAUGUUGAUCUUGAACACAAGGUGAAAUAUCCCAGAGAGGUGAAGAUUCACAAUAGGAAUUCAACAAUAAUUUCUUUUUCUGUAUAUCCUCUUUUAAGUCGCUUGUAUUGGACAGAAGUUUCCAAUUUUGGCUACCAGAUGUUCUACUACAGUAUUAUCAGUCACACCUUGCACCGAAUUCUGCAACCCACAGCUACAAACCAACAAAACAAAAGGAAUCAAUGUUCUUGUAAUGUGACUGAAUUUGAGUUAAGUGGAGCAAUGGCUAUUGAUACCUCUAACCUAGAGAAACCAUUGAUAUACUUUGCCAAAGCACAAGAGAUCUGGGCAAUGGAUCUGGAAGGCUGUCAGUGUUGGAGAGUUAUCACAGUACCUGCUAUGCUCGCAGGAAAAACCCUUGUUAGCUUAACUGUGGAUGGAGAUCUUAUAUACUGGAUCAUCACAGCAAAGGACAGCACACAGAUUUAUCAGGCAAAGAAAGGAAAUGGGGCCAUCGUUUCCCAGGUGAAGGCCCUAAGGAGUAGGCAUAUCUUGGCUUACAGUUCAGUUAUGCAGCCUUUUCCAGAGAGAAGGGAAAAGGAAAAAUUUUGAAAGGCACCAGAGCAUUCUGUUCUUCUUAACAAGGGCUGCAUUCAAGAUACACUAAUCACAGCUGGACCUGCUCGGGUUUUAUCAGAGCUUAAUUGACCUGGGUAAAGAGAAGUGCCCAACCCCAGCCCACUCCAGCCGUCGUGUCCCACCUAAGUGGGGUGGGGGGACUGAAAAGAACCUGUGAAGUUCACAGUCGAAAAGCAAAGCAAAAACCCACUUGAAGUUAACUGAGAUCUAAUCUAAGACUAUAAAAUGCCUCCCCUUCCCCUACACCUUACCACCGCAUUACUAAAGGCCCAUUUACAGCAGUUGCUUUCACCCAGUACAGCAUAUUCAGCUAUCAAGAAAAAAUUACAAGGCAUACUAAAAGGCAUAAAACACAGAUUGAAGAGAUAGAGGAACUAUCACAAUCAUUUAAAUAUGGCAGGGAUGUUAGAAUUAUCAGACUGAGAAUUUAAAACAACUAUGAUUAAUAUGCUAGGGGCUCUAAUGGAUAAAGUAGUCAGUAUACAAGAACAGAUGGUCAAUGUGAGCAAAGAUAUGGAUAUUUGAGGAAAAAAAAGAAAUGUUAGAGAUAAAAACACUGUAACAUGUGAGGAAUGUUUGAUGGGCUUAAUAGUAGACUGGAUGUGGCUGAGGAAGGAAUCUCUGAGCUUGAAAAUAUCUCAGUAGAAACCUGCAAAACUAUAAAGGUAAAAAAAAAAAAAAAAAGGAAAAAAACCGAAACAGAAUAUUCAAGAACUGUGGGGAAACUACACAAGGUGUAAGAUAGGUAUAAUAUGAAUACUAGAAAAAGAAGAGAGAAAGGAACAGAAGAAAUAUUUGGAGGAAAUAUUUGAAAAAUAAUGACUGAUAAUUUCCCCAAAUUAAUGUCAGAUACCAAACUACAGGUAUGGGAAGCUCAAAGAAUACCAAGAAGGAUAAAUGCCAAAAUCUACACUAGGCCUAUCAUAUUCAAACUGCAGAAAACCAAAGAUAAAGAAAAAAAAUUCUGAAAGAAGCCAGAGGAAAAAAUACUUAACCUAUAGAGGAACAAAGAUAAGAAUUAUAUCCAACUUCUCCUCAGAAACUAUAUAAGCAAGAAGAGAGAAAAGUAAAAUAUUUAAAAUGUUGAGAGAAAAAAACACUAACCUAGAAUUCCAUACCCUGUGAAAUUAUCCUUCAAAAGAGAAGGAGCAAUAAAGACAUUCUCAGACAAAAAUUGAGAGAAUUUGUUAUCAGUAGACCUGCUUUGGAAGAAAUGUUAAAAGAAGUUCUUUAGAAAGAAGAAAAAUGAUAUAGAUCAGAAAUGCAGAUCUACAUAAAGAAAGGAAGAGCAUUAGAGAAUAAAUAAGUGAAAGUAAAGUAAAAGUUUUUCUUUUUCUUAACUGACCUAAUGGAUAAUAGUUUGUUCAAAAUAGUAAUAGCAAUAACAUAUUCAAUUAUAUCCACUUAUGUAUGUAUGUGUGCAUAUAUAUAUGUGUAUAUUUAUAUUUAUAUUAAGCAAAAUGAAUCACAGCAGUGACACAAGGGAUAGAAAAGAGGACUUGGGAGUAUUUUGUUAUUAUAAGGUACUGCAAACCUGUGAAGUGGUAUAGUGUUGUUUGAAGGUGGACUUGGAUUAGUUGUAAAUAUACAUUGCAAAUUCAAGGGCAAAUCACUGAAAAAUAUUUUUAGAAAAGUAUAACUGAUUCCCAAGAAAGGAGAGUAAAUAGAAUCAUUUAGAAUGCUCAAAUAAAACCACAAAAGUCAGAAAAAAAGUGGAAGACAAAAGUAGGAACAAAGAACAAGGGCAACAAAUGAAAAAUAAUAACAAAUAUGGUAGAUCUUAAUUUAACUAUAUUAGUAGUCACUUUGAACAUCAGUGGUCUAAAUACACCAACUAAAAGACAGAAGUUGUUUGAGUGGAUCAACAAACAGACUCAACUAUACAUUGUCUAUAAGAAACCCACUUUAAAUAUAAAGACACAUCAUAUAGAUCAAAAGUAAAGGGAUGGAGAUAGUAUAUCAUGCUAUCGCUAAUCAAAUGAAAGAAGAAACAAUUUCAGACAGCAGACUUCAGAGCAAGGAAAGUUAUAAGGGAUAAAGAGGGACAUUACAUAAUGAUAAAGGGAUCAGUUCUCCAAGAAGAUGUAAUAAUCCUUAAUGCAUAUAUCUCUAACAACAGAGCAUCAAAAUACAUGAGGCAACAACUGAUAGAACUGCAAGAAACAGAUGAAGCCACUAUCACCAUUGAAGACUUCACGACAUCUAUCAGAAAUGGGCAAAUCCAGCAGAAAAAAAAUCACUAAGGAUAUACUGAUGAACUCAAUAACACCAUCAAUUAAUUGGCUGUAAUGGACAUCUAUCUACUAUUAAUAAUUUUUCCAACAACAGCAGAAUAAACAUUCUUCUCAAGCUCACAUGGAACAUUCACCAAGACAGAACAUAAAAUACACUUCAACAAAUUUAAAAGAAUAGAAAUCAUACAAUAUCUGUCCUCAGACUACAAUGCCAUUUAACUAGAACUCAAUAACUGAAAGAUAGCUGGAAAAUCUCAGAACACUUGGAGAUUAAACAACGUAUUUCUAAAUAACAAAUGGGUAAAAGAAGAAAUCUCAAAUUAAAAAUAUUUUGAACUAAAAAUGAAAACAAAACAUCAAAACUUACGGGAAUCAGUAAAAUCAGUGCUUAGAGGGAAGUUUACAGCACUGACUGCAUGUAUUAAAAAAAUAGAUCUAAAAUUAUUUAAGCUUUUACUUUAGGAAACUAGAAAAAGAAGAGUAAAUUAAGUCCCAAAUAAUAAUAAGAAACAAAACUAAAACAAAAGAAAAAAUAAAAAGGAAGUAUAGUAGAAAUCAAUGAAAUUGAAACAGGAAAUCAAUAGAGAAAAAUCAAUGAAGCCAAAAACUGGUUCUUUGAAAAGAUAAAUAAAAUUGAUAAGCCUCUAGCCAGGCUAAGAAAAAAAGAGAGUGGAUGCAAAUUGCUAAUAGUAGAAAUGAAGGCGGGGACAUCUCUGUAGAACCCAUGGAGAUUAAAAGGAUAAUCAAGGAAUACUAUUAACAACUCUAUGCUCACAAAUUUAAUAACCUAGAUGAAAUGGACCAAUUCUUUUAAAGACACAAUAUGCCAAAACUCACAGAAGAAGAAAUAGACAAUCUGAAUAUGUCCACAUCUAUUAAAUAAGUGGAAUCAAUAAUUAAUAGCCUUCUGAAAUAGAAAGCACCUGGGCCAGAUGGAUUCAAUGAUGCAUUCUAUCAAACAUUUAUGGGAAAAUUAUACCAUCUCUACAAUGUCUUUCAGAAAAUUGAACCAGAGGGCCUACUUCCAAUUAGGCCAAUGAAUGAGUUUAUUCUAGGCCAGAAUUACCCUAAAACCAAAACUAGACAAAUAUAUUACAAGAAAAGAAAAUUUUAGACCGGUGUCUCUCUUGAAUAUUGCAAGAAUUGCAAAAGUCCUGAACAAAAUAUUAGCAAAUCAAAUCGAGCAAUAUAUUAAAAUAGUUUUAUAUCACAGUCAAGUGGGAUUUAUCCCAGCUAUGCAAGUUUGAGUCAACAUUUGAAAAUCAAUUAAUGUAGUCCACUAUAUCAACAGACUAAAGAGGAAAAAUCAGGCGGUCACAUUGAUAGAUGCAGAAAAUGCUUUUGACAAAAUUCAACACGGAUUCAGGAUGAAAAAUCCUCAGCAAACUAAGAAUAGGGGUAACUUCCUUGAGAAAGAACAUGUAUAAAAAAACUUGUUGUUAACAUCAUUACUUAAUAGUGAGAAAUUAGAGGCUUUCUCACUAAAUCAGAAACAAGGUAAGGAUGUUCCCUCUCCCAAUUUCUUUUCAACACUGCAGUGGAAGUCACAGCAUGCAACAAUACAAGAAAAGGUAUACAAUACAAGAAAAGGUAUACUGAUUGGGAAUGAAGAAAUAACGCUGUCUUUGUUCACAGAUGACAUGAUCAUCUAUGUAGAAAAUCUGAAAGAAUUGACAAAAAGACUCCUGGAACUCAUAAGUGAUUAUAGCAAGUUUGCAGGACACGAGGUUAAUAUACUAAACUCAAUCACUUUCCUGUAUACCAGCAAUGGACAAGUGGAAUUAGAAAUUAAACACACAGUAUCAUUUACAUUAACACCCACAGAAAAUGAAAUACUUAGGUAUAAAUCUAACAGCAUAUGCACAAAAAUCUAUAUGAGAAAAACUAUAAAACCCUGAUGAAAGAAAUCAAAGUGCUAAAUAAGUAUAGAGAUAUUCCAUGUCAUAGAUAGGAAGACUCAAUAUUGUCAAGAUGUCAUUUCUUCUCAACUUAUCUAUAGAUUCAAUAAAAUCCCAAUGAAAAUCCCAGCUAAAGUUAUUUUGUAGAUAUUAACAAACUGAUUCUAAAGUUUAUAUGGAGAGGCAAAAGACCUAGAAUAGGUAGCUAUCACAGUAUUGAAGGAGAAGAACAAAGUUGGGGAAGGCUGAUAUCAACUAUAUGACAUUCUGGGAAAGUAAAAAACUAUGUAGACAGUAAUAAGAUCACUAGUUGCGAGAAGGCUGGGGGAAGAAGUGGCGAAUAGACAGAGCAGAGAGGACUUUGAAGGCAGUGGAACUAUUCUAUGUGAUACUAUAAUGGUGGAUACAGCUCAUUACACAUUUGUCCAAACCCGUAAAAUGUACAAUACAAAACUGAACUCUAAUGUAAACUAUAGACUUUGGGUAAUAAUGAUGUCAUUGUAGGCUCAUUGAUUGUAACAAAUGUACUACUUUGGUAGGGGUAUUGAUAAUGGGGGAAAGUUAUGCAUGUGUGGAGAAAAGGAGUAUCUGGGAAAUCUUGGUACAUUCCUCUCAAUUUUGCUGUGAAUCUAAAACUGACUAAAAAAUAAAGUCUUACCAAAAAAAAAAGACGUCCAUGCAGUAUCUGAAGUUGAACGACACACACACAUAUCCUCCUCCCAGCCACAUACACAAACACGCUCCAAAAUGAAGUCCCAAGAGUGGCAUGAGUUUUUUUUUUAAACUGGAACUCAUUAAGAGUAUGAUUAAUACUCAUUAUUUUCUUUAAAAAAUGGAGUCUAUUUUAUGUUGCUAGUUUCUAGGUACAUUAUUAAGAAUACUUUACCUCCAUCUGCUGGAAAUUUUAAGCAAUUACAAGUUAUCUUGGUCCUUUUUUUCUGAAGGUAUUCAAUUAUCUUCAAAAUGUAUGGGAUAAAAAAAAAAAUGUAAGGGAAAAACCUGUCUUUCUGUCCUGAAUAAUGUUUCUGACACUUCAACAUGUCAUAUUAUAUCAAUUAAAUAAAAGAACGACAAAAUUA